GCUAUUGUCGCCGUGGGCUGAGCUCGCCGGGCCGGCCCCUCCGUGGGGCCGCGCUGGGACGCACGCGGGUGGACGAGGGGACCGAUCCCGGGCGCCCAUGGCCGGGGCCGCCAUGGCCGAGCGGGGCCGCGUGCCUCCCCCCGCACCCGCGCCCAGCACGGAGGGGCUGCCGCGCGCCUUCCUGCAGAGCCUGCGCACCCUGUUCGACAUCCUGGACGACCGGCGGCGCGGCUGCGUGCACCUGCGCGAGAUCGAGUCCCGCUGGCAGGGCACCGACGCGCGGGAGCUGCCCCGCGGGGUGCUGGAGGGCUUGCGCCAGGUGGCCCCGGCCAGCGGCUACCUGACCUUCGAGCGCUUCGUGGCCGGCCUGCGCACCUCCCUGCUGAGCGCCGACGGCGGCCCCCGGGACCCCACGCGCGCCCCGGCCCGGCCCGGGGAUCAGCCGCCGCCGCCGCCGCAGCGCCUGGUGUUCGCUCCGGCCGACGAGCCGCGGACGGUCCUGGAGAGGAAGCCCCUGCCCCUGGGCGUGCGCGCCCCUCUGGCCGGUCCCAGCGCCGCCGCCCGCAGCCCGGAGCAGCUGUGCGCCCCGGCUGAGGCGGCGCCCUGCCCCGCGGAGCCCGAGCGGUCCCAGAGCGCGGCGCUGGAACCGAGCUCCAGCGCGGACGCAGGGACGGGACCGGGGAGCGGCUCUUCGUGGACUCCGGAUCCUGGAGGGCGCCUCGGCGGGUCUGGAGGGAAAGGGCUUCAUGCUUGUCGCGGUGCAGUGGCGUGCAGGGCCCUGGAGGCGGACUCAGGGGAUGCCCGGCGGGCUCCCCGUGCCCGAGGGGAACGUCGGAGGCACACCAUCGCCAGCGGCGUGGACUGCGGCCUGCUGAAGCAGAUGAAGGAGCUGGAGCAGGAGAAGGAGGUGCUGCUGCAGGGUUUGGAGAUGAUGGCGCGGGGCCGCGACUGGUACCAGCAGCAGCUGCAACGAGUGCAGGAGCGCCAGCGCCGCCUGGGCCAGAGCAGAGCCAGCGCCGACUUUGGGGCUGCAGGGAGCCCCCGCCCACUGGGGCGGCUACUGCCCAAGGUACAAGAGGUGGCCCGGUGCCUGGGGGAGCUGCUGGCUGCAGCCUGUGCCAGCCGGGCCCUGCCCCCGUCCUCCUCCGGGCCCCCCUGCCCUGCCCUGACGUCCACCUCACCCCCGGUCUGGCAGCAGCAGACCAUCCUCAUGCUGAAGGAGCAGAACCGACUCCUCACCCAGGAGGUGACCGAGAAGAGUGAGCGCAUCACGCAGCUGGAGCAGGAGAAGUCGGCGCUCAUUAAGCAGCUGUUUGAGGCCCGCGCCCUGAGCCAGCAGGACGGGGGACCUCUGGAUUCCACCUUCAUCUAGUCCUUGUGGGCCGCGUGGGCCCCCAGGGCCAGCCUGGCACUCAGCCCUUCGAGGGUGGGCGCCCCAUCGCACCCACCCUCUCUGGCUGGAGACCCCCGGCAGGCCCAGGCACAGUCCCGGAGUGGGCGCCUUCCUGCCGCCCUUGCCAGAUGGGCUCCCCAGGCCUGCCCCCGGCUGGUCCCCGCACCGAGCGCUUGACUCCGUUUUGGCUCCUGGUGCUGACAUGGGCUGGGGCUCUCUUGAGUCCGCAUAGUCCGCAGCUACUACUGCCGCUGUCAGUGGACAGUGGGGUACCCCUCCAUGAGUUAGCGUCCCCCCGUUUCCAGCGGUGCCGCCCUGGGUCCCAUCUUCAGGGAAAGGCACUGCCCACGCCAGGCUGCACUUCCAACAACGGGCAGCAGAGGGCGCGGGGCGGCUCCGACGCGGGUCCAAGGGCAGCUUCCCGCUCAACCAGGGCACCAGGACGAGGUGGCUGUAGCUCGGACGGACGGAAGUAGAUGGAGGGGGUGGGGACGGCCUGUAAGCGGGGGGUGCCUGCCUGGCUGGGGAGCCCCAGGGAUAGCGGUCGGACUUCAGGUUCUGGCCAAGGCUGAGGGACCCUGGCUGCAGCGGAUCGGCACGCCGGGUGGGCGAGAGCUUGGCCUGCAUGUGCCUCCCACAGACCCUGGGGUGAUGGCCUUCCCCCUCUUGGCCGGGACGUUGCCCCACGUUGAGUCCCACACAACAUCCUGUGAGCCUGGCUCCCCAGGAGGGCCCCCAGACAGCUCCCAGGCACGUCAUAGGCAAAGCCUGUUCCCCCGACUCAGGAUUUCCAAGGCCUGGGGUCCUGCUCACCCCCCUUUGCUCUCACGCCCAGCCUGUCCCCAGGUUUCAGCUGGGAGAGGCCACCUCCCUCAGCCAAGGAAAACGAGAACCCCCAGGGUACAGGAGGAGGCUGGGGCAGGUCCCCUUGGGUGUCACUCCCUCAGCCCCUGCCCAGGCCCACUCCCGCUGGUGCUGGAGUACGCACUGGUGGGGGGGCCCUGCUCAGCCCAACCUGGAGGGUCCCAGUGUCACCAGAACCAGGGGCACGGCAACAGCAUCGAUGGGUUCUGCAGCCCAGGGCCCCCGAUGCGGGGUCAGUGCGUGGGGGGCGCAGGGCCCCCGAUGCCGAUGCGGGGUCAGUGUGUGUGGGGCGCAGGGCCUCCGAUGCGGGGUCAGUGCGUGGGGGGCGCAGGGCCCCCUCGUGUCCAGGGCACUUUGGUACACUGUCCCACAAGGCACCUGUCUCAGAGGAGGGGCCCUGGCAGGCAGCGUGGCAACUCCCUUCCGGAGCCCAGCUCCAUGCUAACCUGCCCACAGCAACCCCACAGAGCCACAUUCCCUGCUGCACCUGGUCUGCAGGGGUGUCCCAGGACAGGCCCAAGUCAGCCCAGCAUGCAGCUGCCCUCCUACCCUGAAGAUGGGAGUGGGCUUUCCAGGGGACAUAAGGAUGUCAGGCCUGGACCUCCUGGGCAGGAAAGGGUGCAGGUCCUGAGGGCCUGUGCCCCACAGCCCCAGCACCAGGUGGACUGCAGCGCAGUGGGUGGGCCAGUGGCAGCCAGGGAGAAGCCCCCCGUCAGCAGGCUGGGGUCUGCCCACCAGGGCCUCCCCACGUCUGCCUUUGAGGGUGCCUGCCAUGCCCUGGGGGAUCCUGGCAUCUUUACUGGACUGGAAGCAGGAGACAGAACAGUGUCUGUCCCGGGGUGACUUCAUCAGGAGACCGCCCACAUAGAGCUGGACCCCGCAGCUGAAGCGGAAAUGUGAGACAGGCUGGCACCUCCGGAAAAACUGCCUUUCAGCCUUGGUGUUCCGUGCAAGGUGAAAAGAAAUAGGUCCUCCCAGUUUACAGCUUGAAAUCAGGCUAGUGAGUGGCCCUGGAGACCACGAGGGGAGAAUUUAAAGGCCCCGGCUGGCAGGGUCUAGGUGGCUGGCAGAGGCACAUGCAGACCCUGCCUGGAGCCUGCCCUAGGACGCUGGGCGGGUCAGUCUCCGUGCAGGAUGUGAGCAGCGUCCCUGGGCUCUAUCCGCGAGGUGCCAGUAGCGUGUGCAGGUACAUACACGUGCGUGCACACUGUGAUGACACCCGGAAAUGUCUCAGGAUGUUGAAAUGUGUCCUUGGGGGCAGAAGUGUCCCCAGUUGAGAAUCUGCCCCAGAGGAACACACCCACACCAGGCCUCAGGAUUUUGUGUUGAUCAAGUUCCAAGGAAAAGGAACAUCUCAGCCGGGCGUGGUGGUUCACGCCUGGAAUCCCAGCACUUGAGGCCAGGAGUUCCAGAGCAGCCUGGGCAACGCAGUGAGAGACCCCAUCUCUACAAAAAAAAAAAAGAAAGAAAGAAAAUGAGAGAUCCAGGUUUAAAAAUUCAUAAACACCACAAGGAAACAAUACACUAUGAGACCCAGCAGAAGCAACAGAUUGACUCUAGACCCAGAUACUAGAAUUAUCAGAGAGAAUAUAAAGUAACAGUGUUUUAUAUAUCUAAAGAAAUAAAAGAGAUUUCUGGAAACAUGAA